AACCCGGGACUGAGGCGGCGUGGGAAGCGGGCGACCUUAUCUCUGCUCAGCUGGAAAAAGGCCCAGGGUAACACCGGAAGUGGGCUUAUUUGCGCAUCAGCUACUUUCGCUUCUACUUAAAAACGGAGGAUCUGGGUAAAAGAACCGAAAGGCUGUACGAACCUAAGACUUGUCUCCGAUGUCCUUCUCAACCAUCAAUUUCAUAUGCGAGGGAAAACACCUGCUGGGUUCACGCAGAAUAUAAAGGUCUUUGAAAUAAUUCUUGAUCUCUAGGCCAAGGAGUUUUACAUUUUAAAAUAAUCAAGCGUGCCUACUGCUUGCCAGGCCCUGCUCUCGCCUUCACUCGCAUUAUUCAAUUAAUCGACACAGGCCUGUGCAGUGCGUCUUAAUGACAAGGACUCCUACCCUCCACUGCCUGUGUUGGAAUCCUGGUUCUGCCAGUUAUUAGCUGUGUAUCCUGGCCUAAGUUACUCUCUGCCACAGUUUCUGACUCUGUAAAAUAGGAUAAUAGUAUCUACCUUAUACCAUUAUUCUAAAGAUAAAUAAAUUUAACAUAUUUAGGUUGGGCACGGUAGCUCACACCUGUAAUCCCAGCACUUUGGGAGGCCGAAGGUGGAAGGAUUGUUUGAGCCCAGGAGUUCAAGACCAGCCCGGGUAAAAUAGUGAAACUCCCCACCUCUCCAAAAAAAAAAAAAAAAAAAAAUCAGCCAGGCGUGGUGGCAAGCACCUGCGGUCCCAGCUACUCUGGAGGCUGAGGUGGGAGGAGGAUUGCUUGAGCCUGGGAGGUCGAGGCUUCAGUGAGCCGUGAGUGGGGCACUGCACUCCAGUUUGGGCAACAGAGUGAGACCUCGUCUCCAAAAGAACAAAAAAUUUAACGUAUUUAAAGCACUCAGAACAGCACCUGACACAUGGUAACCACAGUAACCAGAGAAAAGGCCAUGUGGAGACACGAUGAAAAGCCCCCUCUGCAAGCUGAGGAGAGAGGCCUCACCAGAACCGGACCAUGCAGGUGCCUCGAUCCUGGACUUCCAGCCUCCAGAACUGAUGGCCGAGCCUCGAUUUAACAACCCCUACUUCUGGCCCCCUCCUCCCACCAUGCCCAGCCAGCUGGACAACCUGGUUCUGAUUAACAAGAUCAAGGAGCAGCUGAUGGCCGAGAAGAUCAGGCCGCCUCACCUGCCGCCCACGUCGGCCUCGUCGCAGCAGCCGUUGCUAGUGCCGCCGGCACCCGCCGAGAGCAGCCAGGCCGUCAUGUCGCUGCCCAAGCUGCAGCAGGUGCCGGGGCUGCAUCCACAGGCGGUGCCGCAGCCCGACGUGGCGCUGCACGCACGGCCGGCCACCAGCACCGUCACAGGUCUGGGGCUGUCCACCCGGACCCCGUCUGUGAGCACUUCUGAGUCAAGCGCGGGCGCGGGCACGGGCACGGGUACCAGCACCCCGUCCACACCCACCACCACCAGCCAGAGCCGCCUCAUCGCCUCGUCCCCCACCCUCAUCUCAGGGAUCACCAGCCCCCCUCUCCUGGACUCCAUCAAGACAAUCCAGGGCCACGGCCUGCUUGGCCCCCCCAAGUCCGAACGCGGCCGCAAAAAGAUCAAGGCGGAGAACCCGGGGGGUCCGCCUGUCCUUGUAGUCCCCUAUCCCAUCCUGGCCUCGGGCGAGACUGCCAAGGAGGGCAAGACGUACAGGUGUAAGGUAUGCCCACUGACCUUUUUCACCAAGUCAGAGAUGCAGAUCCACUCCAAGUCGCACACAGAGGCCAAGCCCCACAAGUGCCCGCACUGCUCCAAGUCCUUUGCCAACGCCUCCUACCUGGCCCAGCACCUGCGCAUCCACCUGGGCGUCAAGCCCUACCACUGCUCCUACUGUGAUAAGUCCUUCCGGCAGCUCUCCCACCUCCAGCAGCACACCAGAAUCCACACAGGCGACAGACCCUACAAGUGCCCACAUCCUGGCUGCGAGAAGGCUUUCACUCAGCUCUCCAACCUCCAGUCUCACCAGCGCCAGCACAACAAGGACAAGCCCUACAAGUGUCCCAACUGCUACCGGGCCUAUUCGGACUCCGCUUCUUUGCAGAUCCACCUCUCGGCCCACGCCAUCAAGCACGCCAAGGCCUACUGCUGCAGCAUGUGUGGGCGGGCCUACACCUCGGAGACCUACCUGAUGAAGCACAUGUCCAAACACACGGUGGUGGAGCACCUGGUGAGCCAUCACUCGCCCCAGAGGACGGAGUCCCCCGGCAUCCCGGUGCGAAUCUCUCUCAUCUGAGCCCACUGGAGGCGCCGCCCCACCCGGCCCACUGGCAGACACAGACCCAGGCAGCACCAGGCCCCAGCUCCCUCCGGGGGCCCUCCAGGAACCACCAAGCUCUCUCACGACCUUCCCAAUCUUCCAGAAAGCUUGGUCCGCAGAAGCCCUGCCUGGUCCAGUCCGGGGGCGGCCAGGCCAACUGCAAGAUUCUGGACUGUUUUGGUGGCAUCCAAAGACGAUCUCAGAGCACUUUGAACCUCUCUGUUGAGUUUUCUUUUUGUUCCCCACCCUUCACUUGCUUCACUGUUUUUUUUUUUUUCGUUUUUUUUUUUUAAGUUUGUUUUGGAAAUAACAGAAAAGAUAUUUAUUGGCCAGGAAGUUGGUGCUGCUAAGACCGAGAAAUUUAAAGAAUCGGACAGAUGGACGCAGAGAACCAGAGGGCAAUGUGGGACCUUCUCUUGCCAUGGCCUCAGGUCUUGAGGGAAGGCUCGGGCCUAGGUUUCUGGACUGCAAAGGGGACCCCCAGGUGGGAGGGGCAGGAAGCAGCCGGAGUGAGCCCUUCGCCCCUGAGUGCCUGGCUCGCACCUCUCGAGCUGUGCCCUGGGCAUCACUGAGCAGAGGGGUGCGGCAGCUUCAGGAGGCAGAAACGAGAGGGGUGGGAGAUCCACAGGACCAAAGGGUGCAGUGAUGGGCUGGGUGGCGGGCCCAGGGAAAUGGGGUGGGGAUGGGCUGGGUAAGACCUGGCCCUCCCCUGCUGCCCUGAAGACCACCCCAGUCUACCUCGGUGCUGGCCAGGAAACCUUUCGGCUACCUCUCCCACCAUCCCAGACUGUGGGCAGGGGGAUGGGGAGGGAGUGGGCCUGGAUCUGGGACCUCCCUCCAGAAUUUCCUCCAGAUGGGGGCAGUGCCCAGGGAGGGGUUAUUUGUCUUCCCUGCCAUGGAGUGGGAAUCCCCAGCCGAGGCCCUAGGCCCCUCAGCAGGGAAGGGAUCCCCGGGGAGGCAGGUCCCAGGAGCAGACCCUGCCCCCAGCCCCCACAGACACACCCCAAUCUGAAAGCCAUGCGUGUCGGUGUAUAUAGGAACCAUGUACAGAGCCCAGAGAAGCCCCCUACAUCCCCCCGGGAAAAAAAAGAAAACUAGACAGAAACUCAUCUAUAUAUUCUGUAUCUGGAGUUCCGUUUUGAAUAUUAACUGUGUUAUUUUUAUACACUUUUUAAGCCUUAACUCGCCAUUGAUUUACCAGUUUAACGUUUCCUGGGGUUUCUUUGCCCAUGGGGUUCUCUGCCCCCACCCCCGGCCCUUUGUUUGACUUGCGUCGUCUGAUACUCAGUAUUGUAGCUUUUUGUCCGCAUGUUACUCCCUGUAAAUACGCUGUUAUACAUACUGUUAACACCCCUUUGCUUUUUCUAUGGGACCUCCAGGCCACCAUAUUUAGAACUAGUUACCUUAUUAAAAAAGAAAAAACAGUCUGUUGGCUUCUCAGUCUGCAUCUUGGAGGCAGGGAGGUGAGGGCAGGUGCCCCUCAGACACUUCAGGAAGGUAGUUUGCAUUCUAUUUAAAAAAGGGAGUGGGGAGCAAAUGAAAAUCAAAUGUGGGGGGAAAACACUAAAGGGGGCAAGAAACAAAGGAAUUACAAACCCUCUGCUCUUUGUAUUUCUCUGUUGUGAAGAAUAAACUGUACCUGCACCCGG